GCGAGCCGGCGAGCGGGCAGAGCUCGGCACUGCGCCGGGGCGCACGGCUCGGGGGACCCAGGCCCAGCUACCUUCCCUCCGCCCCCGGGCUCUGUUCUCACUUUCCAGCAGUGGAAGGACGGGAAGCGGGAGCCAUGCAGUCCGAAUCGGGGAUCGUGCCGGAUUUCGAAGUCGGGGAGGAGUUUCAUGAAGAGCCCAAAACCUAUUACGAACUCAAAAGUCAACCGCUGAAGAGCAGAAAGUCAGAUGGCUUUGUGUUGUUUGACGUGGUUCCUUUUCCAAAUAGAUGACUGUAAAGAUGACCUGAUGAUCCUAUGGACUGGGCUAUAAACUUUGUGCAUCUCCCUUCUUGUGCCUUAAUGGCAAGCAGUUCCGCCGAGCAUCCUGGGGCCUCCAAGCCUCCGAUAAGCUCCUCCAGUAUGACAUCACGCAUCUUGCUACGCCAGCAACUCAUGCGUGAGCAGAUGCAGGAGCAGGAGCGCAGGGAGCAGCAGCAGAAGCUGCAGGCGGCCCAGUUCAUGCAACAGAGAGUGCCCGUGAGUCAGACACCAGCCAUAAACGUCAGUGUGCCCACCACCCUUCCCUCUGCCACGCAGGUGCCGAUGGAAGUCCUUAAGGUGCAGACCCACCUCGAAAACCCCACCAAGUACCACAUACAGCAAGCCCAACGGCAGCAGGUAAAGCAGUACCUUUCUACCACUUUAGCAAAUAAACAUGCCAACCAAGUCCUGAGCUUGCCAUGUCCAAACCAGCCUGGCGAUCAUGUCAUGCCACCGGUGCCGGGGAGCAGCGCACCCAACAGCCCCAUGGCUAUGCUUACGCUUAACUCCAACUGUGAAAAAGAGGGAUUUUAUAAGUUUGAAGAGCAAAACAGGGCAGAGAGCGAGUGCCCAGGCAUGAACACACAUUCACGAGCGUCCUGUAUGCAGAUGGAUGAUGUAAUCGAUGACAUCAUUAGCCUAGAAUCAAGUUAUAAUGAGGAAAUCUUGGGCUUGAUGGAUCCUGCUUUGCAAAUGGCAAAUACGUUGCCUGUCUCGGGAAACUUGAUUGAUCUUUAUGGAAACCAAGGUCUGCCCCCACCAGGCCUCACCAUCAGCAACUCCUGUCCAGCCAACCUUCCCAACAUAAAAAGGGAGCUCACAGAGUCUGAAGCAAGAGCACUGGCCAAAGAGAGGCAGAAAAAGGACAAUCACAACCUGAUUGAACGAAGAAGAAGAUUUAACAUAAAUGACCGCAUUAAAGAACUAGGUACUUUGAUUCCCAAGUCAAAUGAUCCAGACAUGCGCUGGAACAAGGGAACCAUCUUAAAAGCAUCCGUGGACUAUAUCCGAAAGUUGCAACGAGAACAGCAACGCGCAAAAGAACUUGAAAACCGACAGAAGAAACUGGAGCACGCCAACCGGCAUUUGUUGCUCAGAAUACAGGAACUUGAAAUGCAGGCUCGAGCUCAUGGACUUUCCCUUAUUCCAUCCACGGGUCUCUGCUCUCCAGAUUUGGUGAAUCGGAUCAUCAAGCAAGAACCCGUUCUUGAGAACUGCAGCCAAGACCUCCUUCAGCAUCAUGCAGACCUAACCUGUACAACAACUCUCGAUCUCACGGAUGGCACCAUCACCUUCAACAACAACCUCGGAACUGGGACUGAGGCCAACCAAGCCUAUAGUGUCCCCACAAAAAUGGGAUCCAAACUGGAAGACAUCCUGAUGGACGACACCCUUUCUCCCGUCGGUGUCACUGAUCCACUCCUUUCCUCAGUGUCCCCCGGAGCUUCCAAAACAAGCAGCCGGAGGAGCAGUAUGAGCAUGGAAGAGACGGAGCACACUUGUUAGCGAAUCCUCCCUGCACUGCAUUCGCACAAACUGCUUCCUUUCUUGAUUCGUAGAUUUAAUAACUUACCUGAAGGGGUUUUCUUGAUAAUUUUCCUUUAAUAUGAAAUUUUUUUUCAUGCUUUAUCAAUAGCCCAGGAUAUAUUUUAUUUUUAGAAUUUUGUGAAACAGACUUGUAUAUUCUAUUUUACAACUACAAAUGCCUCCAAAGUAUUGUACAAAUAAGUGUGCAGUAUCUGUGAACUGAAUUCACCACAGACUUUAGCUUUCUGAGCAAGAGGAUUUUGCGUCAGAGAAAUGUCUGUCCAUUUUUAUUCAGGGGAAACUUGAUUUGAGAUUUUUAUGCCUGUGACUUCCUUGGAAAUCAAAUGUAAAGUUUAAUUGAAAGAAUGUAAAGCAACCAAAAAGAAAAAAAAAAAGAAAGAAAGAGGAAAAGAAAUCCAUACUAACCCUUUUCCAUUUUAUAAAUGUAUUGAUUCAUUGGUACUGCCUUAAAGAUACAGUACCCCUCUAGCUUUGUUUAGUCUUUAUACUGCAAACUAUUUAAAGAAAUAUGUAUUCUGUAAAAGAAAAAAAAAAUGCGGCCUUUUCAUGAGGAUCGUCUGGUUAGAAAACAUAACUGAUACCAACCGAAACUGAAGGGAGUUAGACCAAGGCUCUGAAAUAUAAAGUCUAAUCUUGCUCUCUUUUAUUCUGUGCUGUUACAGUUUUCUUCAUCAAUGAGUGUGAUCCAGUUUUUCAUAAGAUAUUUUAUUUUGAAAUGGAAAUUAAUGUCCUCUCAAAGUAAAAUAUUGAGGAGCACUGAAAGUAUGUUUUACUUUUUUUUUAUUUUAUUUUUGCUUUUGAUAAGAAAACCGAACUGGGCAUAUUUCUAAUUGGCUUUACUAUUUUUAUUUUUAAAUUAUGUUUUACUGUUCAUUUGAUUUGUACAGAUUCUUUAUUAUCAUUGUUCUUUUCAAUAUAUUUGUAUUAAUUUGUAAGAAUAUGCAUCUUAAAAUGGCAAGUUUUCCAUAUUUUUACAACUCACUGGUGGUUUUCCGCAUUCUUUGUACACCCAUGAAAGAAAACUUUUAUGCAAGGUCUUGCAUUUAAAAGACAGCUUUGCGAAUAUUUUGUAAAUUACAGUCUCACUCAGAACUGUUUUUGGACACAUUUAAGGUGUAGUAUUAAUAGGUUAAAACCAGGCUUUCUAGAAAGAAUAAACUUACAUAUUUAUUUUUAGGACAUGAAAAUAGCAAUAUUCUUGGAGAUUGAUAACCAUAGCAUUAAUACGCCCAUUAUGGUCAUUUAAAUUGGGGUUUAUUUCAGCAAACUUGUUGAAUUUAUUUUUAAGAAAGAAAUACUGUAUUGGGAAGUUACUGUUACUUGAUAACAAUGUUUUAACAAGAAGCAAUGUUAUAAAGUUAGUUUCAGUGCAUUAUCUACUUGUGUAGUCCUAUGCAAUAACAGUAGUGUUACAUGUAUCAAGCCUAGAUGUUUUAUACAGAUGCCAUAUAGUGUUAUGAGCCAGGCUGUUGAAUGGAAUUUCUCAGUAGCAGCCUACAACUGAAUAGCAAGUGGCAUAAAGCAUAUCCAUUCAGAAUGAAGUGCCUUAAAUAUAGCAGUAGUCUUUUUUGGACUAGCACUGACUGAACUGUAAUGUAGGGGAAAGUUUCAUGAUGGUAUCUAUAGUCAAGACGAACAUGUAGCAUGGUGCCUAUGUAGACAAUAUAAGAGCUUCCAAUUUUCCUUCAGAUAUUUUUAAUAUUAAAUAUAUUUUAGUGACAGAGUGCCAACUUCUUUCAUCAGGAAACCUUAUUCAGGAGGGUUUUUAAAAAGUGUUUAAAUGUCAAAUGUGAAUUGGUGAUGGGUGAUGGAGGGUUCAGAGAGGAGUGAUCGUCAGAUGUGUGAAUGGACGGUUUAGGUGAAAAUAAUCAACUGCAUAGUUCCCAUGCACGCUGGGCAAUGAGAAUCCUUGGAAACAUUGGUGAUGCUAUCAGUUUUAUAGCUUUAUUUCUUAAGGGGGUAGGGAAAAUUAGUUCCCAUUCUUUCAACCCCCUUAACUGUAUAGCUCUUUUCCUAGAAUAGUGACGCAAAUCUGCAUGAACAGCUAAUUGUACCAUAGUGUUCAUUGAUACAAUCAUAGCAUUGUCUAUUUUUCUCUUCAUAUUUAUAUGGGGGGGAGGGCGCUGGAUGCAAAAGUUGAAGAUCGUGAUGCUAUGAUGUUAGUUUUCCUUAGCUGAUUUUGAGGGUUUUUAAAAAUAAAGCAAGGUUGACUAACCUACGGCCACGGGAACAGGACCAUGGUUAAGCAACCAUAUAGAAAGCUUUGUUGAAAGAAAGUAUGGCAUCUUGUACCACUGCCCUGACUGUCACAACUCCUAACCUUGCCAUUGCCUGCCUCCCCCUCCCCUUCUCCUUAAGAGACAAUUUCUGCAGGUGGCAGGUGAGCAAGCCCAGGAGAAUGCUGCAAUCUUGGGGGUGGUUUUAUUUAUUUCUUUUUUGCCAAAUAGAGUGUGGAUUCAUUUCAGGGGCUAGCUAAGCCAAGAGGCAGUGGUUUGGGCUUGUUGUUUGUAACAAGAAAAUGAUCCACACCACUCCCCCGAUUCCCGGGUGCAGAAUUGUAACUCGGGGUUGGGCCUCUAUAUGGAGUGACCAAAAUGCCAAAAUUGUCCAUCUGCCUCUGAGUAGGGCAAUGGAAAUACCAAACCUUCUGACUUUGCCAAAAAGCAUACAAGCAACCUGGUCAUACAUAGGAUGACAAAAUUCUUUCUGGUUGUUUUUAAACAAUAAAGCAAUAAGAACAAAUACAAUACAUAGGAAGUUAAAAGCACAAAGGAAUGAACUUAUUAAUAUUUUUGAAAAAUGCACUGGGAAAAAGUUGAUGUCAAUAACAGUAUAAAACAGCCCUAUUUCUUGAUAAAAAAUGACAAAUGACUGUCUCUUGCGGAUGCUUGGUACUGUAAUGUUAAUAAUAGUCACCUGCUGUUGGAUGCAGCAAUAAUUUCUGUAUGGUCCAUAGCACUGUAUAUUAUGGAUCGAUAUUAAUGUAUCCAAUGAAAUAAUCGACUUGUUCUUGAUAGCCUCAUUAAAGCAUUUGGUUUUUCA